AGUGUCGGGCGCAGACGGCGGCAGUGCGGCUUGCUCUUGGAAGUUCAGGCUCGGUUGUCUUUUGGGAGCCAUGGAGAGUGACUUUUAUCUGCGUUACUACGUGGGGCACAAGGGCAAGUUCGGCCACGAGUUCCUGGAGUUUGAGUUUCGACCGGACGGGAAGUUAAGAUAUGCCAACAACAGCAAUUACAAGAAUGAUGUCAUGAUCAGAAAAGAGGCUUAUGUACAUAAAAGCGUGAUGGAGGAACUGAAGAGAAUAAUUGACGACAGUGAAAUUACCAAAGAGGAUGAUGCAUUGUGGCCUCCUCCUGACCGAGUGGGCCGGCAGGAGCUUGAAAUCGUCAUUGGAGAUGAACACAUUUCUUUUACAACAUCAAAAAUUGGUUCCCUUAUUGAUGUCAAUCAAUCCAAGGAUCCAGAAGGCUUACGAGUAUUUUAUUAUCUUGUCCAGGACCUGAAGUGUUUGGUCUUCAGUCUUAUUGGAUUACACUUCAAGAUUAAACCAAUCUAGACUGAAUAUUGGUGUGGACAUGGGGGGUGGGUGGGAGUAGAAAAUUUUGUGUAUAUCAGGGCAGUAUUUUUUUAUGAACUAUAAAUGAUUGUCUUUAAUAAAUAUGUGAUAAAAUCCAAUUUUUAUUAUUUUAUAAAGACCUGAA